GUAAGUGUGAGAAAUUUGGCAAUAAAACCACCUAUCUUUACAGAUUUUGGGAAGUCCAAAAUGAUUAGCUCAGUAAAACUCAAUCUCAUCCUAGUUCUGUCGCUGUCCACAAUGCAUGUGUUUUGGUGUUAUCCAGUUCCAUCUUCUAAGGUGUCUGGAAAAUCUGAUUACUUUCUCAUUCUGCUGAACAGCUGCCCAACCAGAUUGGACAGGAGCAAAGAACUAGCUUUUCUAAAGCCAAUUUUGGAGAAGAUGUUUGUGAAAAGGUCCUUUCGCAAUGGAGUUGGCACAGGGAUGAAAAAAACUUCCUUUCAAAGAGCAAAAUCAUGACUAAGUGUGCAAAGGACUCGGGGAAUUAAUCUAACUGUAGAGUGUGACUGACGUACUCAAAGUCCAUCGUCUCUUUAUCAUUGAGUGUUGGCAUGCUCUCUAUUCUCAAAUAUCUUUCCUCUCCUGACUGGUACAGAGUAAAUUGAGUAAAAAAAGAAAAAAAAUGUAAACAUGUCUCAAACCUGUCUCAAACUUCCACUUGUGAGAGAAAAAACAAUUUAUGUGGUCCAUUAGUAACUUUUUCCUGAAUGGGAUGGACACUUUUGCUUUGCUUUUAACUUGGCCAGAAAGCAUGAGCAUGUUGACAGUCAUCACGAUAGUAUGAUUUUUUUUUUCCUGCCUGUAAUAUCAUAACACGAAUACUGUGAUAUUUGUUUUUCUUUUUAAUACCGUUUUCUCAAAUGACUUAACAGGCUCAAUUCUUGGGGUGGGGGGAUGUGCUAUUUCUGUUUCUAAGGGGCUUGUGAAGUUAACCAAAAUUAAGGUGAAUGGUACAGCUGUAUCAAUUGAUUAAUUAAUUGAUACCAAGAACAAACAUCCCUGGAGCACUCUAGAUGUAAUUCUUGUCUCCCUUUUCCUAUUCCAAAUAUACUUAGCUAUAGGGUGUUGUUUUGUUGUCUUGUCUUGGAAAUUUGUUGCCUUUUAAAAUCUUUAAGCACAGAAAUGCUGCCAGUAACAACAACAACAGAGAGACUGAGAGUGCCCUGUGUUGUCAGGGCAGCCAUUUGGAAACCUGUUCCCCAAACUAUGCUGAUUAAUGCCCUCUCCUUUCCCCCAUCCUUCCAGGAAAGACUGCCCACUCUUUGCACUGAAACUCCUGACACUCCUUUUUUAAAAGGAUAAUGCGACAUUGGUUGACGUGUUAUUUCAAAUGCAUAAUGUUAAUAAAUCUGUUCACGCA